GCCCCGCCCCUCGGCGGCUCCAGGUGCGGCUGUGGGACCUCGGACCGCGGCGGGGCCGGGGCCAGGGCCGGGGCCGGGGCCGGGGCGCCAUGGCCGAGUCCCAGCUGAACUGCCUGGACGAGGCGCACGUGAACGAGAAGGUGACCGAGGCGCAGGCCGCCUUCUACUACUGCGAGCGGCGGCGGGCCGCGCUGGAGGCGCUGCUGGGCGGCGGCGAGCAGGCCUACCGCGAGCGGCUCAAGGAGGAGCAGCUGCGGGACUUCCUCUCCAGCCCGGAGCGCCAGGCCCUGCGGGCCGCCUGGAGCCCCUACGAGGACGCCGUCCCCGCCGCCAACGCCCGGGGCAAGAGCAAGGCCAAGGCCAAGGCCCCCGCGCCGGCGCCGGCUGAGUCCGGCGAGUCCCUGGCCUACUGGCCCGACCGUUCCGACACCGAGGUGCCUCCUCUGGACCUGGGCUGGACGGACACUGGUUUCUACCGCGGCGUGAGCCGGGUCACGCUCUUCACCCACCCGCCCAAGGACGAGAAGGCGCCGCACCUCAAGCAGGUGGUCAGGCAGAUGAUCCAACAGGCCCAGAAGGUCAUUGCUGUGGUCAUGGACCUCUUCACUGAUGGUGAUAUCUUUCAAGACAUUGUGGAUGCUGCCUGUAAGCGCCGGGUCCCAGUGUACAUCAUCCUGGACGAGGCAGGAGUGAAGUAUUUCCUGGAGAUGUGUCAGGACCUGCAGCUCACUGACUUCCGGAUUCGGAACAUCCGUGUCCGCUCUGUGACAGGCGUCGGCUUCUACAUGCCCAUGGGGAGGAUCAAGGGGACCCUGUCAUCAAGGUUCCUGAUGGUGGACGGUGACAAAGUGGCCACUGGAUCUUACAGGUUCACCUGGAGUUCCUCCCAUGUGGACAGAAACCUCCUCCUGCUCCUGACAGGACAGAACGUAGAGCCCUUUGACACGGAGUUCCGGGAGCUGUACGCCAUCUCCGAGGAGGUGGACUUGUACCGGCAGCUGAGCCUGGCGGGCAGGGUUGGCCUCCAUUACUCCUCCACUGUGGCUCGAAAGCUUAUCAACCCCAAGUACGCCUUGGUGUCAGGCUGCCGCCACCCGCCUGGGGAGAUGAUGCGCUGGGCUGCCCGGCAACAGCGGGAGGCGGGCGGCAACCCGGAGGGGCAGGAGGAGGGCGCCAGCGGUGGCGAGUCGGCCUGGCGCCUGGAGAGCUUCCUGAAAGACCUGGUUACGGUGGAGCAGGUGCUGCCCCCCGUGGAGCCCAUCCCCUUGGGAGAGCUGAGCCAGAAGGAUGGCAGGAUGGUCUCUCACAUGCACAGAGACCUGAAGCCCAAAUCCCGAGAGGCACCCAGCCGAAACGGCAUGGGAGAAGCGGCCCGGGGGGAGGCCGCCCCCGCCAGGCGCUUCAGCAGCAGGCUCUUCAGUCGCCGAGCCAAGAGGCCUGCGGCGCCCAAUGGCAUGGCCAGCUCUGUCUCCACCGAGACCUCUGAAGUGGAGUUUCUGACGGGGAAGAGGCCCAACGAGAAUUCCAGUGCUGACAUCUCAGGUAAAACAAGUCCCAGUUCUGCCAAGCCUAGCAACUGUGUGAUUUCCUGAGCUGCGGGAUGGUGGUGGGCAGGACGUGUGGAUGCCUGCCUGCCCUGCCCUGUGCUGUGGAGAGCGCAGGUCGCACACUGCACCAGUUUGCACAUCAGACGCCAACUGGCCUUCUGCCCUGCAGCCUCCGUCCUGGCCUCAGGGACGCUGGAUCCCAAAUGAGAGGGUCCGAAGCAUCUCAGUCACACGCCUCCACCGGACUGUCGGUGGCUGGGCAGGGGUCAGUGCCACGGCCUCCUUGUUUACAUGAAGUGGAAGCUUGACCAGUGUCUGCUCGCCUUUGUGCCCCACCCCCUCCGCUGAUUGCCAGAUGGGGUGAGGGCCCAUUCUUUAAACCUUUAUGGGGUGGGGUGUCUGGGGCAGCUGCAGUGGCUUCUCCUUUCCCAGGCUUCCUGGUGCUUCUGGUUCCCCACGCCACUCCCCACCCAAGAGAUUGGUGGAAUAAAAGGGAAGAGGGCAGGGCCCUGAGCCUGGGAUCCCAAGUUCCAGUCUUUCUCUAGCCUCUGAACUCCAGAUGUAAGGUGCAGCUGGAACUGCAGGGGCACUGGCUGCAGUGGCCUUCCUGGCCCCAUCCCUGCAGGCUCCUGAACUAGACUUGAAUGAGGGUAAGAUCCUGCGGCCUCCCGCAGUGGGGGCAGAAUUUGACACUGCUUUUCUGAGAGCGCUCGCACUGAGGUCUCUUUUUCCCUGCCCAGUGCCGUCCUGGCAGUCUCGGCAUGGGUGGUUGAGACCUCCUUGGCUGCUGCCUGCUGCGGGCCUAUGUGGGGGUCCUUACAGGGCCUUUACCUGGGACUGCUCCUUCCCUCAGUCAGUAAACUUUGGUUUACAGCCCAAGGCAGGGAGGGAGCUUGGCUGAGAGGGGAUUGGGGGUGUGGGAGGCUGGGCCCUGAGGACAGGAGCAUUUGCCUUUUCUCCCUCAACUCUAACGGGGUCCUCGGACCCCUUCACCAACCAGGGCUUCCAGGUUACACUUUGGCCAGACUGGCCUUUGCCUCCUGCGAGAGUCAGGCCAUUUUUAGGAGCCUGUGCCUCGCCAGAGCAGGUCAGCCUAAUGGCCAUGAGGCUGAGCUGGGAGGCCCAGUAAGCAAUUCCAUUCUGCCUUCCCCACUUGGGUGACUGGAGAGGGCCGAGGAGAGUUUGUGAAUGGACCUGGGAGAAAUUGCCAAACUGCAGACUCUGUGAGCCGGCCCUGCCGGCAGGGCGAUGGGGGAUCCAAGCCCUGUGGAAGAGCCAUGCAGCGGACUUUCUUGCCCUCUGACCUCUGAACCAAACUCUCAUCCUCUUUCUUUCCUUCUAAAAAACCCUAGGACACUACCAGCACCUGGGGGAGGGGUACAGAUGUCUGCAAGGCAGCUGAUGUGAGAGCAAGAAAAGGGGCUGCUCUGGCUGGGCUGUGGGAGCCAGGCAUUGCUUCUGAGGAAGCAGGAAGUGGGGACCACAUGUGGCGGCCAUUGAGGAGAUGCAAUCUCUCUGGCAGUGGGGAGGGGAAGGGAAAGGAAGGGUGAGCCUGUCCCCAGGGUCUUCUCUGUUAAUCCCAAGGCUGGCUUCUAGGGCGUGUGGAGAAGGGACUCUGGCCCACCUCCCUGAGCUUUUAUGAAGGUGAAAUGCUUCUGGGAAGUGUUUCCUUAGGCACCAAGACCAGGCAGUGUGGCAUGAGCUCAUUCUGGAGGGGAGGGAAGGGAGAGAGGGGGGAGGUGGGAUGUGGGGGUGUUACACCUCAGCUCGAGGCGGACACCUUGAAGGUAUGGGACAUGAAAUGUGUAAACUGCAACGCGGCAAAGAGAUCACUCUCUGGUGUGGAGGGUGGGUGUCUCUGGGGAUUAGGGAGGCAGCCUGGGGAAGGGACCGGCCUCCAAGCAAGUCAGCCAAGGGCAUCUGUGCCUCCCCUGCCAGAAGAGCAGGCCCUGCUUUGUCCCUUUACCUCCUCUAGGCCCAAAGCACACCCAGGUCCCUCCCCUGCCCUGACAUCUAAUCUGGGAGGAUCCCUGAUUGGAAUCUCCAAGUCACCACAGCCUUGAGCCAGGCCUUCCUUUCUGCCUCAGUUUCUCCAUGUGCCAAGAUGGCGUUUUUCACACUUUCUUGGUAGAAAUGAUGGGGAGACCAUAUGUUAGGAAGCAAGUUGGCAUAGUGGGAAGAGGGCCAGCCACAAGGCAGGAGUGCCCAGGCAGGGUGCCUCUCCCUGCUGGCCUGUGUCCUCGUCCUUAUAGCAGUGUGGACAAGAUGGUGUCGGCACCCCCCGCUCCAAAAGGCUUGAGACAGAAACUGUAGUCCGAGAUGGCAAGGAUUUUGAACUCACAAAAUGCAGCUCUUCAUGUUUGCCUGUCUGCCUAGGCACCGGCCCACUCUGUUCUGCCUCUUGGCUUCUCAGCUGUGAGUACGCCUGCCCUCUGUUCCAGCACUUGCACAUACUUUGUGAAGCAGUCUCUUACUCAUCAAAUCUCAAGGGUACAUCUGGCCCUCCCAGUUGGAUGGCAAGUUCAAGGGUGGAUCAUGCCCUUGGUCCCUGCACAGCAGCUUCUGCAAGGCUGGUUACAUUGGAAGGGCUCUAGGAGGAACAGGAUAAGGCAGCACUCUCGGGGCUGGGGUCUGGCUUCACUGCACCCCCCUCCCACCCCACACCACCACCAAGCUGCUGUCUUUCUGAGUCAGCUUCUGUAGGGUAAGUGUUCACAGCUGGUGCAGCUCUUUGGGAAACCUAACCUCCCAGUGAGCUGAGCCCCUGGUGCGGCCGCCACGCUUGCUUCUGCCCCACAAGGGCAGUAAGCACAGGACUUCUGGAUGGAUCUGGGAGCCUGCCCCUUGGGAUUUGGCAAAACUUCCCAUCUCCUUAGCUACCUGUCCUUAAUCUUAUCCCUGACCCCUCGAGGGCUUUCAAGAUAGCCUCUGUUAACAUCACUACCCUCUGCCUGUGUAGAACUUUAUAGAAAGGCUAGGCAAAAAAUGAGACCCAGAGAUAUGGAAGAAACUGGCCAAAGAGGGGAAAGUGGGCUAUUUCUUUUUUUUUUUUCUUUUUUUUUUCUGAGACAGAGUCUCACCCUGUUGCCCAGGCUGGAGUGCAGUGACAGCGAUCUUGGCUCACUGCAAGCUCCGCCUCCCGGGUUCACGCCAUUCUUCUGCCUCAGCCUCCUGAGCAGCUAUGACUACAGGUGCCCACCACCAUGCCUGGCUAAUUUUUUUAUAUUUUUAUUAGAGACAGGGUUUCACCAUGUUAGCCAGGUUGGUCUUGAUCUCCUGACCUUGUGAUCCGCCCGCCUUGGCCUCCCAAAGUGCUGGGAUUACAGGCCACCGUACCCGGCCAGGCUAUUUUUUUGUUUUGUUUUUGUUUACUACUGUAUUGCUUUUCUCUUUUUCAUAUUUAUUGAGCACCUACUAUAUGCCAGUCACCAUGCUAGAUGCUUUAGUAACAUGAAGGUUUCAAACUAAGAAAAGCUCAACAAAGAGCCCUUUAGAAAGGUAACAGUUUUCCUGUGUAUUGGGGGAGUGGGUCUCAUAAGGUUGUAUGAUGAGAAGCGCAAGUAAUUGUUUUGUUUUUUUUUUGAGACAAUGUCUUGCUCUGUCGAUCAGGCUGGAGUGCAGUGGCGUCAUCUCAGCUCGCUACAACCUCCACCUCCUGGGUUUAAGUGAUUCUCUGGCCUCAGCCUCCUGAGUAGCUGAGAUUACAGGCACGCGCCACCACGCCCGGCUAAUUUUUGUAUUUUUAGUAGAGACAGGGUUUCACUAUGUUGGUCAGGCUGAUCUUGAACUCCCGGCCUCAGGUGAUCUGCCUGCCUUGGCCUCCCAAACUGCUGGGAUUACAGGCAUGAGCCACCACGCCCAGCCUGGCUAAGGUUCAUUAUCCCCAUCUUUCAGAUGAGGAGGCACACAACUCUCCCCAGAUCCCACGUCACAGAGAAUGCAGGUCUGAGUCUGUUCCUUGAGCUCAGGGUCUUGGCAAUGGUGAUGCUUUGGAGCUGCAGAAUCCUCUGUUGGGGAUGGGGCUGCCCUGUGCAUUAUAGUACGUUUAGCAACAUCCCUAGCUUCCACCUACUAAAUGCCACUAGCACUCCUUCAGAUGAGACCACCAAAAAUGUCUCCAGAUGUUACCACAUGUCCCCUGGGGGGUAAAAGUGCCCCCGUUGAGAGCACUGGCUCUUUUCUUCACAGUCCUGACCUGGUGGCCUGCACAGGCCACUUCUCCGAAGUGUUUCAAUGCACUCUCUGCCCUGGGUACCUUGGACACAGCACCCUGGCCCAGAGAGGUUGGCUGACUUGCCUGAGACGCUGCUUCCUGGGAGACGCAGUAGCAUCUUUCCUUUCUGUUCUGGUUAUCUUUCUUAGUUCUUUACCACCUUAUAUUCCCCAUGACAGGUGUGUUUAUGUACACACAUCUGCCUCACUCCACUCAGCUCCCUGUCAGGUUUCCUGCCAGUCUGUCCCUCUUCCUUCAGGCUCAGCUACGUCCUGCACAGACAGUACCACUGCACAUACCUGUGUGUGCCCAGCGGUGGACCCACCUCCAAAAGCAGCCAGUGCUGACAGCAGAGAGCCUUCCACACUCAAGUCAGGCCAAGCAGGAAUCGCUACCUGCCUGUCAUGACCACAUUCUCAGUGAACAUUGACAAAGCCCCCUUAGCAGCUAAUUAGCCCUGCCGUGCGCUAGGGAUGCAAUUUCUCAUCUGGCAGUGCGCCACACUCCUGCCUCCCUGCCCAAAGGACGUAGUGGCUGCUGCUGAUCGUCUGCACUGCUGUUCCAGGGGCAGGAGGUUUGCUGCAAAUCAGGUACCCCCAGCUCAGUGAGCAGAACCAGUCCAAGGUUGAGUGAGGAGAAGGGCAAGAAGGGCAGGCACAGCCGUGAGUAUGUUCUGGGGCUAAGUAACCAUGAGAUCAGCCCAGAGACCUUGCACAGUUAGGCAGGCCUGGACUUCUCGCCCUUCCCCUUGCAGCUUCUGCUCUCCCAGCUAGGGACUGAGGAAAGCCCUGCUUCUAGAUGCCAUGUGCUGCUGCCUGGCACGAUAGGUACCCAUCUGUCCUUGGGGUUCCUGAGCCUGGAGAGCGGGCUUUGUGAGCACUGGUGCCUCACCUGCCUGGCUCAGCUCUGCAGCCACAAUAUAUGCUUAAUACCUAUUUGUUAAAUGAUUGAAGACUUGACUGCCAUUCAGUACAGAGAAUUAGCCAGGUGAAUAAACAGGAUGUGUCAUAGAGGUUCUAGAAUUGAUCAUGACCCUUUCUGUCUCAUUCCUGACUUCUAAUACCGUAUAUGCCAAAUGGGGUUCUGCUGUGAUUUAAUUUCUUAAGGACUGGGUUUAUCAAAAGUCCCUCCUGAUCUAAUCCUUUCCUCUAGGAAGGCUUCUCCUUUCUUCAUCUGUCCUAAGUGCAUGGUCUUCAUCUCCUGGGUGGUCCAGACUAGGUGGCACUGGGCCUGCAGGCCUCUAGCUGCUCAAGGAUGGCCCUGUCUGCAUGCUUCCUUUCAAAAGCUAGCAUAGAAAGGAGGGCCCAAGGUGAGGAAAUUUGUCCAAAGUCACCCAAUGAGUCGCAGGAAGGGCUAGAAUCUGGUUAUCUGGACCGUCCUAGAGCACUUUCACAGUGACAGCCGGCUGGAAUCAAGUUUUCAUUUAGAAAAAUGGCUAGAAGUUAGGGCAUUGCCUGCAGCCACUGAAAAGCAGCUUUAGGAGCAGAUGUCCACGUAAUAGAAGGAGAUGGGCUAGGGCCUGCCACGGAAGCCAGCAAGCGCGUGGGAGCUGGGGGAGGAAAGGAGCAAAAGGCAAGAACAGGCAGUAUGUCCGCGGUGCCCACAGUGCUGUGGGUACAAGCAAGGGGAAAAGAGCCCAUGGUGUGCAGAAAACCAUGCGUCAUGAUUCUUAUUUCCUGCUCGCAGCUUUGACUCUCUGCCUCAUCUCUUCCUGGAAGUGUCUUGGAAGUUAGGCGACUGCACAGGGAAAGGUUCGCUGCAGUGCUUGCAGGCCUGCACCCAUUUAUUCAUCCGGUGGAUAUUUGCUGGGUGCCCGGCCUGGGGAUCCAUGGUGAGCGAGGAAGGCAUGGUAUUGAAGUGGUAUGCCUGCAUGACCUUGGCGGGGGCGCAUGGCAUAGAGAGGACAGGCUUCAGAACAGGCAGGCAAGGGCUGAAAUCCUAUCUCUGCCACCGAACAGCUAAUGACCCCAGCAAGCAAUUUCACAUCCCCGAACUUUCCUGUUUCCUCAUGUGUCAAAUGGGGAUGAUCUCGAGACGACUCUCCAGAGUAACCACGUGAAGCACCUAGCACAGGGGCUGACGCAAACAGCUGGGCAUCGGAGGAGCCUCCAGGGUUGUGACCUCCAGUGGCUUAUUUUCCUUUUGGGAUCUUCUCUCCUAGAUCCUCCCCUUUAAUUCCCUGUGAAAUUUACCACUUUCAUAUUGAAUCGUUGGCACACAGGGCUAACUGCUUGUUCACCUGAAGGAAGCUACAGAGUUCAGGUUUCUUUUUUCUUUCUUUCUUUCUUUUUUGCUUUUUUAAGAUGAUCUUGCUCCGUCACCCAGGCUGGAGUGCAGUGGCGUAAUCAUGGCUUCCUGCAGCCUCAAACUCCUGGGCUCAAUGAGUUCCUUGAGAUCUUCCAUCCUCAGCUUCCCAAGUAGCUAGUAGUAGUAGUGGCUUGCACCAACGCUCCUGCCCUAAUUUUCAAUAUUUUUUUGUAGAGAUAGGAUCUCACUGUGUUACCCAAGCUAGACUUGAACUCCUGGCCUCAAGCGAUCCUUCCGCCUUGGCCUCCCAAAGUGUUGGGAUUACAGGCAUUAGCUACCACACCUGGCCAAGGCCCAGGUUUCGACAGAAAGGGAGAGAAAACCUGCCAGAGAUGCCAUUUCGGAGCCACUCUGCUUGGCAGGGACCUGUGUUCCCCUCAUGCAGGUUCAUCCUUAGAGGGCUGCGGUCUUAUCUGGUUGUGCAAAAGUCCCACAACCUUUCUGGAUUGAUAGUUUGUGGUGAAAUAAACAAUUUUAGUUUGUUUGGAGAAUCUUUUGUAUACAAAAUACAAAUAAAACCUAAAUCAAAGAAACAGAGCAUGUCCGGAGAAGUCUGCCAACCCUUCUCCAGGCCAUGGGGCUUCCCAAGCCAGGCCUGUACUCCUCAUGUAGAUUCCACACCCCGCCUUGAUGUCUUUGGCUUUCACACUAGUGACUAUAGCCUGGUGGGACGGGGUCUAGGGGCCACAGUCCUGGUCCUGCGCAGGUGGCCCUGGAGAGAAGCCUUGGAGAACUUGGAGAAGCCCACGCGGCUGGCAGCAUCAUGGUGAGAGGCUGACACCUUGUGGCUGGCUGGCAGCAUACGUCCUUCCUCCCCUAGGUCAGCUAGACGGCCAAAGCAGGGAUCUGCAAGCUCCUUCUGUGGCGGGCCAAAAAGUGAACAUUCAGUGUGUCUGUUGCAGCUACUGUCAUAGCACUGAGGCACCCCUAGACAGUACAGAAACAAGCAGGUGUGGCCAUGUUCCAGUGAAACCUUAUGAAUACUGAAAUCUGAAUCCAUAAUUUUCAUGUAUCACAAAGUAGUAAUAUUCUUUUAAUAUGCAAAAACCGGCCAGGUGCGGUGGCUCAUGCCUGUGACCUCAGCACUUUGGGAGGCCGAGGUGGGUGGAUCACCUGAGGUCAGGAGUUCGAAACCAGCCUGGCCAACGUGGUGAAACCCUGUCUCUAUUAAAAAUACAAAAAUUAGCCUGGUGUGGUGGCACAUGCCUGUAAUCCCAGCUACUCGGGAGGCUGAGGCGUAGGAAUUGCUUAAACCUGGGAGGCGGAGGUUGCAGUGAGCUGAGAUCAUGCCACUGCACUUCAGCCUGGGCAACAGAGCUAGACUCCAUCUCAAAAACAAACAAACAAAAAAACAAAAGCAAAAACCAGUCUUAGCUCACAGGCUGUGCCAAAACAGGCAGUGGGCUGGAUUUGGUCCUCAAGCCUGGGCUUGCUGACCUCUGGCCUAGGACACCUCUCCUUUAUGCCUCCGCUCCCAACACGGACUCUCAACUCUCAUGUUUACCUUGUCAUUGUUCUGUCAAGAGGAAUUCACUAGUCUCACUCCUCCAACCAGACCGCUGCCACUAAGGCUUCUUCUGAACAGAAAUUCUGGAUUUGUUCUCACCCAUUUCAUAAAUGUACAUAAGCACCCAUCAGGUGCCAAGCCCUGUGCUGAGAUGCCUGCAGAGCCCAGAGUUUUCACCAACUUUUUUUUUAAGAGAUGGGGGUCUCUGUUGCCAGGUUGGAGUGCAAUGACAUAAUCAUAACUCACCGCAACCUCAAACUCCUAGGUUCAGGUGAUCCUCCCGCCUCAGCCUCCCAAGUAGCUGGGACUACAGGCAUGCACCACCCUGCCCAGCUAAUUAAAAAAAAAACUUUAGGGAUGGGGUCUUGCUAUGUUGUCUAGGCUGGUCUCUAACUCCUGGGCUCAAGUGAUCCUCCCACCUCAGCCUCCCAAGUAGCUGGGCUUACAGAUGUGAGCCACUGCACCUGCUCAACAUUUAAUUUUUUCAUUCAUUCAUUCGUUCAUUCAUUUGUUCAAACGAACUUAUUGAGAACUUACUGUGUUCCAGGCACUGUGAUAAGAUAGACCUGGCCUUUACCUUCAAAUGUUCAGAACAUGGUUAGGAAGAUGGAUACUGGGAGGCAAGUGUUCUGAUGGGAAAGCACAGCAUGUAAAGAAGCCCAGAGGAGGCACUUAACCUGGGGGAGAAGAACAGGGUAGGCUUCCUGGAGGAGGAGGUAAUCUCUGAGCCGAUACCUGAGGAGUGAAUGGAGGAGGGGACAAUGAGGCAAGGCAUUCCAGGGAAAGGUCCAGAGCCUAGACAGAACUCUUUUAGGAGAAUUAUGAGAAUCACAAUUAUCGAGGACACAGUGAAGACUCAGAUAACUCAAAUAUAGGUUUUGCCCGCAAAGCCUUCCUGUCUGGUGGGUGAGACAGUCUACAGCAAGCUGCUCCAAGGAUAUGGAGAAAAAAGUUUUUCCUCUGGCCUUGUAGGAUUGGUUAUUACUGAGCCUGGAGUACGCAAAGGCCAGCGAGUGCUCCUAAGGCAGGGAGGGGGCUGCCUUCACUAUGGGUGCUCAGGAAAUCUGCCAGGGGAAGGGAGAUGUGGGCCUGCCUCGGCUGCAGAAACCCCUCAGAGGAGGAGGAGGGGCUUGAACUGAGCUUUGAAGAAAGUGUAGACUUGGGGACAGGCAGAGGAAGAGGGGGCAUCAUAGGCAGCAGAAACCACAUGGACAAACUCUCUGCCGGAGAAUGGGCAUGGCCGGGCUGAGGGGUCCCUGGACAGGAACCAGCCUUCCCUAUGCACCUGCACCCGUGAGUCUCACAACAGCCCCAACAGGCAAGUGUUAUUUUCCUCAAUUCUACCAAUUAAAAACUGACCUUGGGCAACUGCUUAACCUAUCUCUGCCUUACUUUCUUCAUCUGUAUCUACCUCAGAAAGUUACUAUGAGGACUGAAUAAGCUCAUACAUAUACAAUGCUUGGAGCAGAGGCUGGUACUAGAGCUGGCUUCAUGGGCAUGAAACCUGUGAACACAGAACCCCAUGCUUUCAUUUUCCACUUAGUCCUGCCUGGCAUAGUAUGCAGUUUUUUUAAUUUGAGAUGGAGUCUCCCUUUGUUGCCCAGGCUUGAGUGCAGUGGCGCGAUCUCAGCUCACUGCAACCUCCACCUCCCAGGUUGAAGCAGUUCUCCUGCCUCAGCCUCCUGAGUAGCUGGGAUUACAGGUGCGCGCCACCAUACCCAGCUAAUUUUUGUAUUUUUAGUAGAGAUGAGGUUUUGCCAUUUUGGCCAGCCUGGUCUUGAACCUCUGACUUCCAUGAUCCACCUGCCUCUGCCUCCCAAAGUGCUGGGAGGAUUACAGGCAUGAACCACUACGCCUGGCCUGGUAUGUGGGUUAAAAUGUUAGGUUUUAUCAUUAUCUUAGGUGGAGAAUAACAAAUCCGAUUCAAUAUAUUCAUUUUAGAAACGAGGAAACUGAAGCUUAGAUAGUUUGUGUGACUUGCAAAAAGUCACGCAGCAAACAAGCUGCAGAAUGAAGGGUGGAGAUGGAGAGAUAGAAUUCUCAUCUUAGAGGUGAAAGUAGGAUAAUGACCCAGCUGAGCUUGCUGAGUCCUGCGAGCGUCGCACGCCCCCAGAGACAACAUAAGGAGAGAAGUGCAGACAGAUUCCUUUGAAGGAGCUUAGAGAAAGAGAUGGUAGGGAAAAGAGCAUGAACAGUUGUAGAGGUAGGAGGAAAGCUGGCUAUUUGGGGAAGCAAAGAAAAGAUUCUCAGAGUAAAACGUAUUGGUGAAGCCAUGGAAACAAGGACUGAGAAAGUCUCUUGGAUCUUGGCCACAAAAAGGUUAUAGAUGAGCUUAGAGAAAUGAAUUUCAGUAGAGUUAGGGCUAGAAGCCAGGUUCAGAGAGAGAAAACGAGAGAGCAUUCCUGGUGGUGGAGAUGGCCGCAGGCCAUUAUUUAAAAAGCUAGGAUAAGAAAAUAGAGAAGAAAGGGAAGGAAGCUAUUUGAAGGGAGUGGGAGAAAAGCCAGAUCUCAGUUGGGACGUGGAGGAAGGACCACCAGAGGCAGUAAUUUAGCCGGAAAGAGGUGUAUUUCUUUCCUUGAGUUUAUAGGGGGUAAAGAGGAUGGGGCUGAGAUACUAAAGACUACGAGGACAACUGUUCAUUGAGGGCUGGUCAUCUCCCCAGCUGCACUGUGGGGUUCCCAAGUCAGACAUCCCAGAGGCAAUAUAGCAGCGUGGACAAGAGCUUACUCGUUGGAGUCAGACCGCCUAGGUUCAACGAUGGGUUAGUUAGCCCUUCAGUGCCUCCAUUUUCCUAUCUAGAAAAUGUGGAUAACAAUGGUUGUUGUGAAGAUUAACAGCCAUAAUCCACGUAAAGCCCUCAGUACAGUGUAUGACACACAGCAAGUGUCCACCAAAGGGUAGUUAUUAUUAACCAUAAUCCUGGUUCUCUUGUGAGCUGCCUCCUGUGUGUCUAGCAUUGGCCAGCACACAUGAGGGGGUCCAGUGUUUGCUGCUUAACUAAGUAGCUUCUCAGGAAGUGUGGUCAUAAAAAAUGAUAGGUGAUUUAGAAGGUGAGACAGACACAAGGGAUGUGUUGCACAGUAAAUGCUCCCAGACAUGCAAUAAAUGCUUAUAAGCAUGCCCUCUGUAAUCAGCCCUCUUUAGAGAGUUUCCCUGCCUCAUUGCUCUUGGUCUUUGGCAAUGGCUACACCCACUGCCCAAGCAAGCAGUAUCAGCUGUCAGCUGUCCCCUUGUCUUUUGGAUCAGAUUCCUUUACAGGGAUCUUCCCAUUGUUAUAAGCUUCAAGAAUUGGAGAAUGCUUAAUGAACACUUCCAAAUUCUUCAUAGCUAUGAGGGGCCAGUGCAAAGGGCGGAAGGAGUUCUUCUGUGUCACAGAAAUUAGAGCUGGAGCAGAUCCAGCUUGCUAUCCCCCCUUCCCCCAGCUUGUGGGUUAUUGCAGAAUUGUUCACAAAAAUUCCCAUUGCCUUGGAAUUUGUCCAAGCCGAGGGCAGGGAUCACAACACAACCUCUCAAGGGAAAAAAGGAAGGCCUGUUGCUUGAGAUGGCUCAGAGCACUUUUGGUAGCCAGCCAAGGCAGCUAUCACUCAUGAAAUCUGCCUUCCCCUCCAGCAAAAAGCCAACUGUAUAGAACACCACAUAUAGAGCGCUAAGAAUAGCACAGCGCUCCAAGAACAUAGUGCACUUGGCCUGCAUACAAGUGUGCAGGGCUUAACGAGUCUUUUUACUCUGAAAGCUGGGUGGGUUGGAACAAACAAACAGAAAAAUAUUUUCCCCAAGUAGCAUGCAGAGAGGAAAUGAGAGCAAGCACAAGAGAGCACCCUGGCAUAGCAUUCUCUGACCUGGGCUGCCUUUUCAGGGUAUGAGUUGAUUCCGCAGGCACCAAGGCAUGCCUGUAAGCCCUACAGGGCAGACGCCCUCACCCCAAUCAUUGGCUUAACAUUCACACCAGGCUGAGUAAGCCCCAAAAGUCCUGCCAUUGGCUCUGACAGGAAUUGAAACCCAUCUUCUCCACAAUAAAUAUUUGAUUGACAGAUUGGCUUCCUUCCUAUAAGUAUAGAAAGCGAGGGCAGGUUCCAUCCAAAGCCGCAGUUCUGGGUGAUGAGAGCUCUGAGAGCCCAGAAAAGACCCUGAACCACAUCCCACUGUUUGUUGGAAGAAGAAACUCAUUUGUGGGUCUGUUCAUAAAAGAGUCUGGGAAGAUAGUCUCCUUAACAGUGUCUGGAUGUAACAGACUAUGGGCGGCUUUUACUUUAUAACUUUCUAUAUUGUCUGAAAUACAGAAUAUUAAAUAUUGAGUUAAUAUUAUAUUUACUCAAUGUUACUUUUUUUUUUUUUGAGACAGGGUCUUGCUCUAUUGCCCAGGCUGGAGUGCAGUGGUGUGGCUCACUGCAGCCUUGAACUCCCAGGCUCAAGCAAUCCUCCCACCUCAGCAUCCCAAGUAGCUGGGACUGUAGGCGCAGGCCACCAUGCGCAACUAUUUAUUUUCUUUCUUUUUGUAGAAAUGGGCUCUGCCUGUGUUGCUCUAGCUAGUCUCAAGCUCCUGGCCUCAAGCAAUCCUUCCGCCUUGGCCUCUCAAAUUGCUGGGAUUACAAGCAUAAGCCAAUGUGCCUGGCCUCAAUGUUACUUUUAUGAUCAGAAAAACGGCCAUCUUAUUUGGAAAUUAUUUUCCUAUUCUCAAGUGGGCAAAUAGGAGAAGGUUUCAGGCAUUUGUUUUGUCUCUGGGAGGGAAGGCACAAUGAGGUGGAGUGGACAAAUUGCUGAGGCCUUUAUGGACAAAGAUUCUAAGAAGAACAGGCUUUGGCCAUCUCUGGAUAUUCCCAUUCUGCUCCCUGCCACCAGAGAGCAAAUGUCGUAGGUCACCACACAUCACCAGUCUCUUGCCUAGCUAACCGUAACUCAUUCUUUAGUUCUCCUUGAAGGUGUCACUUCUUCCAGGAAGCCAUUUCUGUCCCUCCCGAGAUGGAGUCCCAUGUCCCUACCAUUUGCUUCCAGGGCACCUUCUCACAGCACUGCAUCAUGGUUAUCUGCUUAUCUGCUGGACACCCCUACUCGACUGAGGUCCUUGAAGGAAGAGAGAGUGUAUCACUCAUCUGCAUAGCCUUUGUAACUUAGUAAAAGUGCCUGACAUGCUCACUAAACAUUUACUGAGUAAUUAUUUAUUUGGGGGCCUUUUACGAUCAGAACAAUGUGAAGGACACAAAGAUGAAAAAGAAACCAUCUGCUUCAAGGUACUUACAACUGAAAUGUAUCAAACAAUUACCCAGAAAGUCAAGCACCAACUUAAGUGCUAAAAUAGGGGUCCAAGCAACCAACUUUGAAGAUUAGGAAGGUUUUAGAUUCUGAAUGUUUCUCAUUCAUUGUGUUUUUGAGUUCAGAAUCCCCAUACUGGAAGGCUAAUAUGGGGUAUGUGCAUACAAUUUUAAGGACUCACGUUCUUACAACCUAUAUUAGAAUUUGACGCACGAUCUUUCUUCUGUCCUUCUUGCAGUUGCCCUAGGAAUACAUGCCACUUACUCUUAAUUGACGUUUAUGAAAUACCUUGGCUUCAUUUGCUGAAAGGCUCUAAGUGUUGAGCAUUGUUACUAUGUUACAAUGGUUGUUUUAUUAUUAAAGCAGUGCCAAGGAGGUUACACAACAGCUUGGAUCAGGAAGUGAAACAAGGGCGGUGAUCCCACUGAAGCUACAGGGGAUGGGGAUUUGGGACGGUAAAAUGUUAAUUACCCAAGAUGGAAUGUGGGCUAGAGUCCAGCGUUGUGCUCCUGGAGAUCAUUUCGGUCGCAAAAGCUCACUGGCAAUGGGUCCUAAGCGUCCUGCCCUCCUCUGGCUGAAAUGUUGGAUUCACUUCGAUGAAUGCUGCUAUAGGGAAAGAACCCAGUGGCCACCAGCCAGGAGCACACGUCUUGCUCAGCAUCAACUAUCCUGGAAGAUUUCCAGGAGCUGAAGGGCUGUUCUCUUUGCAUGCAAUAAAUUAUUCAUUUCUAAGACGA